AGAGCCAGCUUUCCAUCCUCUCACCUCAGGGCCCCUUUCACUCCCUGGAGUCCCACAUCUUCUUUUGCCUUGAGGCACCUCCACGCCUCCACUUCACCUCCCCGGCUUCUAAAGUCCUCAGGCCAGGUUCUUGGUCCCCCAUGCCACCUUGCCUGGUCUCCGACCUGUCCCUUUCUCCAAAGGACUGCCCUACAUCUGUAGGGUUUCCCGUCCCCCUCCUUCCCCAGCCACGACUUCCUCACCUCUCACAGAAGACCCCAAACCUUCCUGCUUAGAGGUCCCCGAGGCUCUCCAGGGGGCUGCGAGGGGCUCAUGGGAUCCCCAUGGGCCAAGGCCAGGUGGUUGACAUGCUGAAGAGUUUCUGGCAGAAGGUUUGCGGAAUGAGAACCUCAGCGCUGUUGCAAGGGAUCACAGAGACCAUAUUCUACGGGGCUUUCAGCAAAUCAAAGCCAGGGGGAGACAUUGGACAGGACAGCUCUGAUGAUAAUCACAGCGGGACUCUUGGCCUGUCCCUCACAUCCGAUGCACCCUUUUUGUCAGAUUAUCAGGAUGAGGGAAUGGAAGACAUCGUAAAAGGAGCUCAAGAACUUGAUAACGUAAUCAAGCAAGGAUACUUGGAGAAGAAAAGCAAAGAUCAUAGUUUCUUUGGAUCGGAGUGGCAGAAGCGAUGGUGUGUUGUCAGCAGAGGUCUCUUCUACUACUAUGCUAAUGAGAAGAGCAAGCAGCCCAAAGGGACCUUCCUCAUUAAGGGCUACGGUGUACGGAUGGCCCCCCACCUGCGAAGAGAUUCCAAGAAAGAAUCCUGCUUUGAACUGACCUCCCAGGAUAGGCGCAGCUAUGAGUUUACAGCUACUAGUCCAGCAGAAGCCAGAGACUGGGUGGAUCAAAUAAGUUUCUUGUUAAAGGAUCUGAGCUCCUUAACCAUUCCAUAUGAAGAGGAUGAGGAGGAAGAAGAAAAAGAAGAGACAUAUGAUGAUAUUGAUGGUUUUGACUCCCCAAGUUGUGGUUCCCAGUGCAGACCCACUAUCUUGCCUGGGAGUGUGGGGAUAAAAGAGCCUACAGAGGAGAAAGAAGAAGAAGAUAUUUAUGAAGUCUUGCCAGAUGAAGAGCAUGAUCUAGAAGAGGAUGAGAGUGGCACUCGACGAAAAGGAGUAGACUAUGCCAGUUACUACCAGGGCCUAUGGGAUUGCCAUGGUGACCAGCCAGAUGAACUGUCCUUCCAACGGGGUGACCUCAUCCGUAUUCUGAGCAAGAUGAAAGUUUCUAAAAAGACUUUGUGGCAAGAAGCAAGCCCUGAUGGAAAGGUUUGUGGGUUUUUUUUUAAUAACUUUUUAUAUUCUUAUCUAAAACAUCUUCAUUGAACAAUUUUGUAUAAUUUAAAUCUUAGCCCUACCAUUGAGAAUAUAUGUAGAGUUAUGGAAUAGUGAGCAUGUAUAAUUCUGAAGCCCUAACACAGUCACUUGUAGAUGUGCAUCCCUACCUUGAAGACAGAAACACUUCCAAAUUGAGGAUUUCAGGUCUCCUGGGAGCCUCUCAGCAUUUUUCCAAUCUUUCCAAACAUCUGGGCAAAGAGAAAUCAGACUUUAUAGAAAACAUUGAUCCCAGAAAUUCAGUUCUCUUUGCCAUCCUAAAACUAAAACUCAAGAAUCAGCAACUUAAUAAAAAUGCAGUAAAUUAGCACCUUUAGACAGGAGCAGGGUUCAUUCAGAGCUGGGGUCUGCCUGACUGAGCCAGUACUCUCUCCAUUUUAAUAGUUUAAUAAAAAUUAGCAUAAUUAACGAACAUCUGUAUGAUCCAGAGUGGUGCAAUUUGGCACUUGGAAACGAGGGCUUAAACAUGAUUGCUGUGAGUUUAAUGUUGUUUUAAUUCUUUUUGGCACUGUGCAGUGAAAUAAACGUUUGGUGGUGAUAGUU